GAGUCGCAGCCAGCCUGGGAGCUGGGCCAUGUUGGCCGCAGAUGGCCCCCUGGUGAAGGUUCCCGUUGGCUUUGGGAAGUAGACAACGGGUCUGCCUCACGGGGCUGAGGUGGGACUGGAGGAUUUCGAGGGCAGAACUCUGGGAAGGAAAGAAAGGCUUAGGACCCAACCAGCAUUCCCCCUGGCACUGCGGGGGCCUGGCCAGCUCAUGGCGUUCCCUGAGCCUGUUCCCCAACUGUGAAAGGGGGUGAUGAUCUUCACCUCCCGGCAUCCUGAGCGGCCAAGCAGGUUGGGGGCGCCUGCCCCCCACUAGGCCAAGUGGAGGGGGUCCCUCCGUCCAAUGGGCCUGGCCAGGGCCCUACGCCGCCUCAGCGGCGCCCUGGAUUCGGGAGACAGCCGGGCGGGCGAUGAAGAGGAGGCCGGGCCCGGGUUGUGCCGCAACGGGUGGGCGCCGGCACCGGUGCAGUCACCCGUGGGCCGGCGCCGCGGUCGCUUCGUCAAGAAAGACGGGCACUGCAACGUGCGUUUCGUAAACCUGGGUGGCCAGGGCGCGCGCUACCUGAGCGACCUGUUCACCACAUGCGUGGACGUGCGCUGGCGCUGGAUGUGCCUGCUCUUCUCCUGCUCCUUCCUCGCCUCCUGGCUGCUCUUCGGCCUGGCCUUCUGGCUCAUUGCCUCGCUGCACGGCGACCUGGCCGCCCCGCCACCGCCCGCGCCCUGCUUCUCACACGUGGCCAGCUUCCUGGCCGCCUUCCUCUUCGCGCUGGAGACGCAGACGUCCAUCGGCUACGGCGUGCGCAGCGUCACCGAGGAGUGCCCGGCCGCUGUGGCCGCCGUGGUGCUGCAGUGCAUUGCCGGCUGCGUGCUCGACGCCUUCGUCGUGGGUGCUGUCAUGGCCAAGAUGGCCAAACCCAAGAAGCGCAACGAGACGCUGGUCUUCAGCGAGAACGCCGUCGUGGCGCUGCGCGACCACCGCCUCUGCCUCAUGUGGCGCGUCGGCAACCUGCGCCGCAGCCACCUGGUCGAGGCCCACGUGCGUGCCCAGCUGCUGCAGCCCCGUGUGACCCCAGAGGGUGAGUACAUCCCGCUGGACCACCAGGAUGUGGAUGUGGGCUUUGAUGGAGGCACCGAUCGUAUCUUCCUCGUGUCCCCCAUCACCAUCGUCCAUGAGAUCGACUCUGCCAGUCCUCUGUAUGAGCUAGGACGUGCCGAGCUGGCCAGGGCUGACUUUGAGCUGGUGGUCAUUCUCGAGGGGAUGGUUGAGGCCACAGCCAUGACCACACAGUGUCGCUCGUCCUACCUCCCUGGUGAACUGCUCUGGGGCCAUCGUUUUGAGCCAGUUCUCUUCCAGCGUGGCUCCCAGUAUGAGGUCGACUAUCGCCACUUCCAUCGCACUUAUGAGGUCCCAGGGACACCGGUCUGCAGUGCUAAGGAGCUGGAUGAACGGGCAGAGCAGGCUUCCCACAGCCUCAAGUCUAGUUUCCCCGGCUCUCUGACUGCAUUUUGUUAUGAGAAUGAACUUGCUCUGAGCUGCUGCCAGGAGGAAGAUGAGGACGAUGAGACUGAGGAAGGGAAUGGGGUGGAAACAGAAGAUGGGGCUGCUAGCCCCCGAGUUCUCACACCAACCCUGGCGCUGACCCUGCCUCCAUGAUGCAAACUGAUGUCCCCUUCCCCGUGUAUGCCCCCUUCCCCAAGGUAGCAAGAUGGAGGGAUGGGGCUCUCUCCUGGGAUGGGGGCAGGUGUUCCUGAAUACCGACAGGCCUGCUGGGUAAAUGACUAGGUGGUAAGGUUCUGCCAUGCCUGGUGACCCACCAUGGACAUACUGGACCUUAAUUCCUCUGCUUCUGUGCUCCCUCCUGAGAACCCUUUAUGAGCCUGAUUCCUCAGUCUCACCAGAAUUCUGGAUCACCCAAGAGGAAAAGACUGGCAGUUCUAGAUUCCUCUAUAUGGGGAGACCUGGAUUGUUGACCAGGGUGAGAAGCCAAUGGUAUAGACUGCCUCUGGGGAAGCAAGUUGGCAGUUCUUGAACAGCAUCAGAUAUCAAGAGUUUGUAGGUCUGGAUUCACCUAAGAUUCAAGGGAGUGUUGCUUCUCAACUCAGCCAACUGAGUAGCAAAUCAUUUGUUCUAGACCACCUAAGGAGGGAAGGUUAUGGAAUGCCCCAAGUAUUCAAGAUCAUCUUGAUUGACCAAAGACCAAAAAAAAAAAAAAGACCUGUGGUUCCAGAAAGCUCAUUAGUUGAGAUUCUGUGAGUCUAGGUUGACCACAGAGGCAAGCACUGGUGAGUCUAGGACAGAUUUUACGUGGAGAGUUGAACUACUCCAGAAACUAAAGAGUAAUGUUUCUAGAAUGCACAAAACAUUGUUAGUCUGUGGGUUUAGAAAGACUGAAGUGACAGAUUAAGAGUUCUUGAUAUUAGAUAACUCCAACUUCUGGCUGUAGAGCACCCAGCCAAGAGAAUAAGCAGUGCUUUGAAAGGAUCCACUGGGUGGGUUGUUUUUUUUUAAAGUGCCAUUCUAGAAUGUCCAAAGGGAAUCAGGAUUCUGUGGCUGUAGACUGAUCACAGAGUCAAGGAAGCAGUGGCAAUUCUAGAUAUCUGAGAUUUUGCUGGUUCCAGUUUGCCCAAUGGAGUUGAGAAUCUCAAUGAUUCUAGAUGACUUCUUGUGGUUCUGUAAUGCCAAAAGGAAUGAAGGCUCCAGGGAUACAGAGUUGUCCAUUACCAAAGCCUGGAAGUUCUCAUCACCUCCAGGUGGACUGCUUGGCAGUGCUAGGAGGUGGACUCAGGACUUCAGAAGCAACAUUUCUGGCCUGACCUGGAAGGUGAAGGUGAAGGUGAGACCCUGUAGGGCACAGGGCUAAUUAGUGGACAAGGGAAGGGGGAGGCCCAGGGCUGGUGAGUCUAGAAUGCUCUGGAACCCUACACCUAGUGAUGUGUGUCUAUUUCUUUUUCUUUUUCUUUUUUUUUUUUUUUUGAGACUGAGUCUCGCUCUGCCGCCCAGGCUGGAGUGCAAUGGCGUGAUCUCAGCUCACUGCAACCUCCGCCUCCCGGCUUCAAGUGUUUCUCCUGCCUCAGUCUCCUGAGUCGCUGGGAUUACAGGCAUGAGCCACUAUGCCUGGCUAAUUUUUGUAUUUUUAGUAGAGACGGGGUUUCGCCAUGUUGGCGAGGUUGGUCUUGAACUCCCGACCUCAGAUGAUCCACCUGCCUCGGUCUCCCAAAGUGCUGGGAUUACGGGUGUGAGCCACCAUGCCCAGCCGUGUGUCUGUUUCUUAAAGAUAUUAUACAUAUGUAUAUUAUAUAUAUGUAAUAUAAAUACAGAUAUCUAUCUAUUUUUUCCCUUGGUCCCUACAACAGGCUUAGAGAUGGAGUGCUAGCUAAUUGGAAUGAGGUCCUUUUCAAGGACCCCAGAAGCUUUGCUCUAAAUCCCAAUGCUGCCCCAACUUACUGUGUCACUUUGGACUCCUCUUCAUGUCAGUUUCCCCAUCUGUAAAAACGGGAUAUUGGAACUUGAAGUUCUUCAGGGGCCUUUCCAGCAGGAUGAGUCCUCACUACACCAAGGGUGGGAUGGGCAUUCGAGUCCUGGGGAUUUCCCUCCUCUCCCCAGUGCUGGAUCAUACGGCCUUCCAGGAGACGCUGGGAUGUAAGAUACUCUUGGAGGCUGGCUCUGAACUCGGGUGUCUGAAUCACAGGGCAAGGGUAGGCGUGGGCUGUGGCUAACAGCCAGAGUCACUUCCCUGGCCUAGCUUGGGGACCUGGGGAGGAGGAGGUAGCUCUGGACACCAGGGUUCUUCCCAUUGUGGGAGAGUGAGUGUUUUAGGGGGAGACCUGUCCCCCAGAUUAAAGAACUGGGAGCCCUA